GCAGAUAGCUCGGCCGCGCGUCUCAGCCGCCGGGGCCCCGAGCGCAGGCGGCGAGGCCACCACACCUGCAGAGCGCUCGGGCUGCCUAGCCGGCACCUCGCCUCCCGCCGCGCAAACCCCUUCUCCCCACGCGCCGAGUCUCCCAUGACGCCCGAGCCCCCCGGCCGGCGACAAUGACCACUUCCCUGCAAGAUGGGCAGAGCGCCGCGAGCAGGGCGGCUGCCCGGGAUUCGCCGCUGGCCGCCCAGGUGUGUGGCGCUGCCCAGGGGAGGGGCGACGCCCACGACCUGGCGCCGGCCCCCUGGCUGCACGCGCGAGCGCUCCUGCCCCUUCCGGACGGGACCCGCGGCUGUGCUGCAGACAGGAGAAAAAAGAAAGAUCUUGAUGUUCCGGAAAUGCCAUCUAUUCCAAACCCUUUUCCUGAGCUAUGCUGUUCUCCAUUUACAUCUGUGUUGUCAGCAGACCUAUUUCCCAAAGCAAAUUCAAGGAAAAAACAGGUGAUUAAAGUAUACAGUGAAGAUGAAACCAGCAGGGCUUUAGAUGUACCCAGUGACAUAACGGCUCGAGAUGUUUGUCAGCUGUUGAUCCUGAAGAAUCAUUACAUUGAUGACCACAGCUGGACCCUUUUUGAGCACCUGCCUCACAUAGGUGUAGAAAGAACAAUAGAAGACCACGAACUGGUGAUUGAAGUGCUAUCCAACUGGGGGAUAGAAGAAGAAAACAAACUAUACUUUAGAAAAAAUUAUGCCAAAUAUGAGUUCUUUAAAAACCCAAUGUAUUUUUUUCCAGAGCAUAUGGUAUCUUUUGCAACUGAAACCAAUGGUGAAAUAUCCCCCACACAGAUUUUGCAGAUGUUUCUGAGUUCAAGCACAUAUCCUGAAAUUCAUGGUUUCUUACAUGCGAAAGAACAGGGAAAGAAGUCUUGGAAAAAAAUUUACUUUUUUCUAAGAAGAUCUGGUUUAUAUUUUUCUACUAAAGGAACAUCAAAGGAACCGCGGCAUUUGCAGUUUUUCAGCGAAUUUGGCAAUAGUGAUAUUUAUGUGUCACUGGCAGGCAAAAAAAAACAUGGAGCACCGACUAACUAUGGAUUCUGCUUUAAGGUGUUACCUUCAAGAUAUGCAUUAACGAUAAACAAUGUGCUGUGGCCUUCUAGCCUAACAAAGCGGGAGGGCCCCGAGACCUGAAAAUGCUCUGUGCAGAAGAAGAGCAGAGUAGGACGUGCUGGGUGACCGCGAUUAGAUUGCUUAAGGUAAUCUCGCCGGAGGCAUGAAUUUCUAUUAACUGCUGUGAGUACCAUAAAAGUUAGAAAAUAUCUGUAUUUCAGAACGUGAAGUCUCACUGGGUGGCUACAUGAGAAAGAAGAAAAAUAACCACCAAAUGUGUAUGUUUUUAAAAUUCUAAAUGAUAAACAUUUUCGGAGUAGAGUGGAAUAACCUAAUACAUUUCUGUUUUGUGUGUGGAGUAAGUAUUCCAUUUCUAGAAAUGUUCUGAUUUUCACUUUUGUGAAGGUAUUACAUAGCCAGUGUAACUGAAUGAAAUGUCUCCUAUACAUGACUAAGUCUGCACUCUUAAAACGUUGCCAACAAUCCAAGGUAAAGUGUAUUUUAAAAUGUGCCCACCCUUGAGAUAUUUAAUGUAACUGUUUUGUGUUCGAUUCGUGUUUUAUAAAUUGCUUUCUAGUUUAAUAAGCAUGACUCAAAUUAUUGUACAAUUUUACUAUGAAUAUAUUUUUUAAACAUCUACUCUCGUGCUAAGUAGAAAUUACAACUUCCGUAAGCAUAAUUUGUUGCUGCUGAGCAAUUUUGAAAUGAGUAACAAUAUUCUAAAGGUAGACUCUCAUAGGAAAUAAAAGCAGAACUGAUGUCUUCCAGAAUGUAUAGAAAGCAUAUUUAUUUUCAAAAACUGUUUGCCAGAAAAUUGAGCAAAACUUAAACUGUAUACUUAUCAACUAUUUCCUUUUAAAGAUACUGAUUUGGUAGUCACAGUUAGGGAGGAAAUUACAAAAUUUUGUUGUUGAAAAGAUACAAUCCAGGGAAAGUGCCCGUCCACAUUAGUUAGUAUUGCUGCUGCUGAAGCCAACAAAAUACAUAAUUUAUUGUUAUUAUUAAAUUUUUGGUUUAAAAUAAGAGCAUUAACAUUUUCUAAGGUACUCUUUAUAAUUUAUGCCUAGGCACUAAUAUAAUUUGCCAAUAUAUUGAUUAUGCAUAUUAUAUGUGUAUUAGAUAUAUAUAAUCCUUUUCUUACCACAGGAAGAUUUAGAUUAUUAACAAUGCGUGUACUAAAACUAGCUUUUCAAUAUAGUUAGAAAUGAAAAUCAGAGAAGCUGGAGCACUGUGAAGUCCUUAGGUUCCCCCAUUUCAUUUACCCUGAAGAAGGGGAUGAAGUAAACUUUUCAAUUGAUUUGCAGUUUGUAUAUUUUCCAGGUGUACUUUUUUUCUUCUGCCUUUGCCAUUUUUACCUCUUCUGCUCUCUGUUGACUUUUUCCUAGCAUCCAACUUAAGAGAUAUCAGGGUAAAGAAGGACAGAAUAGUAAUAAUCAGAAUCAUUAUCAUACCAGGUUUAGAAGAAAGUUUUAUUUUGUAUUCUUACAAUUUUUAAAUUGAGGUAAAAUUCACAAAAUAUAAAAUUAAUCAAACUAUUGUUAAUGUGAAUAAUUCAGUGGCGUUUAGUGCAUUCAGUUCCAAGACAUUUUAAUCACCUCAAAAGCAAACUCCAUACCCAUUAAGCAGCUACUCCCACACCCUAGCAAUCACCAAUUUGCCUCUGUCUGUGUGGAUUUACCUAUUGUAGGUAUUUCAUAUAAAUGGAAUCAUACAGUAUGUGACCUUUUGUUUCUGACUUUUACUUAGCAUAGUGUUUUGUGGUUCACCAACAUUGAAGCAUAUGUUAGCUCUUUAUUCCUUUUUAUGGCUGUGUACUAUUCCAUUGUAUAUAUAGCUCUCUAUAUCUAUCUAUAUGUUGGAUAAACACAGUUUAUCCA